ACUCCAUCCCUGCCCGGGCUUCUGAGGCGUCUACCUUCCCAGUCCUAGGACUGAUCUCCAGGACCAGCACUCUUCUCCCAGCCCUUAGGGUCCUGCUCGGCCAAGGUAGGGGGAGUCACGCUAACCGCAGAGGGAAUGAGUAGGGGAUGGAGAGGAUGUGGAGGGACCAGGGAAAACGGGUGGUGUGGGAUGGAGUCGAGGGGAAGCCACCCAACUGAGAGUUUGAUUCUUGUCAAAGGGCAAGUGAGACAGAGUACACGGAGGAGGCACAUACCGGAGGCGGGGGCUACGGGUGUUCGAACAGGGCCGCCAGGAGCGCCCUAAGGGAGGGGGCUCCUCCGGGAGGCGCUGCCCCUGGGUCCCCAACCCAGAACAAAGCUGCCUUGUUGGAUUGAUUGUUUGGGUUGGGGGAAGCAUGUUGACGGGGGCUUGCUGUAGAGGGGCUGUUCUCAGCCCUAGGCAGAGAAGGCCUUGGCUGAGGAGCCAUAGCGCCUGGCCUCCCGUUGCCCGGUGACAGGGAUGGUGGUGUUGGCAGGAGGCUGGGACAACCCUACCCCAUCCCCCGCCCAGCCUUGAGGCCUGGCCCUCCUGGGCCUCUUGACCCUGCAGGGCAUCUGAGAGCCUGCGUGUUGGGGAGGGCGUGCAGCAGGUUCUCCAGGCGAGCUUUGGUGCCAGCCUUCCCUGCCUGGGAAUCUGCUGGGUUAGGACUCUGGGCUCCCAUUCAGGGGAUCUGUGAUCCCAGGGCCGCCUAGGGCCCCUUACGUGCCUCUCUGCACAAUCAGUACAGCUGUCUGUCCUCCCUCUGAGUAAAUGGGGUCAUCUGGAUCCCUCCCACGUCCGCCCCUUGGCUCUUGUCAAUCCCUCUCCUUCUCACCCGCGGUGUGCUUGGUUCCCCUAUACUGAGUGCUUAGUUCUUUGCCUAUCACUUUCUAUCCGUUGUCUCUCUCCUCUGUGUCUUUCUGGUUUUCUCUCUCUCAUUCCCACAGUCUCCCUUCCUCUCACAUCCUGUCUGUCUGGGUCUUCCUCUCUCUCUACGUGUCUCUUGCUCAGUCUCUAUCUCUUUUUAUUGACCCUUCUCUGACUCUCGAUCUCUCAUAGUUGUCUCUUAUCUCUGGGUCUCUCAGGCUGUGCCUCUAUGACCUGUGCCUCAGCCCUUAUUUAAUGUGUUUCUCUCCCUGUCUCUUGGUCCCUGGGGCUCUUUCUCUCCUGUUGUCUCUCGCUGUCUCUGUCUUACUCAGUGUCUGUUUUUCUUUCGUGACUUCUCCCUCUCUUUCUGACUCUGGGCCCCACUCAAUCUGUUUCUCUCACGCACACUUUGUCUCUGGGGCACCCAGGCCUUCCCUGCCAUGCGACCUGUCAGUGUCUGGCAGUGGAGCCCCUGGGGGCUGCUGCUGUGCCUGCUGUGCAGUUCGUGCUUGGGGUCUCCGUCCCCUUCCACGGGCCCUGAGAAGAAGGCCGGGAGCCAGGGGCUUCGGUUCCGGCUGGCUGGCUUCCCCAGGAAGCCCUACGAGGGCCGCGUGGAGAUACAGCGAGCUGGUGAAUGGGGCACCAUCUGCGAUGAUGACUUCACGCUGCAGGCUGCCCACAUCCUCUGCCGGGAGCUGGGCUUCACAGAGGCCACAGGCUGGACCCACAGUGCCAAAUAUGGCCCUGGAACAGGCCGCAUCUGGCUGGACAACUUGAGCUGCAGUGGGACCGAGCAGAGUGUGACUGAAUGUGCCUCCCGGGGCUGGGGGAACAGUGACUGUACGCACGAUGAGGAUGCUGGGGUCAUCUGCAAAGACCAGCGCCUCCCUGGCUUCUCGGACUCCAAUGUCAUUGAGGUAGAGCAUCACCUGCAAGUGGAGGAGGUGCGAAUUCGACCCGCCGUUGGGUGGGGCAGACGACCCCUGCCCGUGACGGAGGGGCUGGUGGAAGUCAGGCUUCCUGACGGCUGGUCGCAAGUGUGCGACAAAGGCUGGAGCGCCCACAACAGCCACGUGGUCUGCGGGAUGCUGGGCUUCCCCAGCGAAAAGAGGGUCAACGCGGCCUUCUACAGGCUGCUAGCCCAACGGCAGCAACACUCCUUUGGUCUGCAUGGGGUGGCGUGCGUGGGCACGGAGGCCCACCUCUCCCUCUGUUCCCUGGAGUUCUAUCGUGCCAAUGACACCGCCAGGUGCCCUGGGGGGGGCCCUGCAGUGGUGAGCUGUGUGCCAGGCCCUGUCUACGCGGCAUCCAGUGGCCAGAAGAAGCAACAACAGUCGAAGCCUCAGGGGGAGGCCCGUGUCCGUCUAAAGGGCGGCGCCCACCCUGGAGAGGGCCGGGUAGAAGUCCUGAAGGCCAGCACAUGGGGCACAGUCUGUGACCGCAAGUGGGACCUGCAUGCAGCCAGCGUGGUGUGUCGGGAGCUGGGCUUCGGGAGUGCUCGAGAAGCUCUGAGUGGCGCUCGCAUGGGGCAGGGCAUGGGUGCUAUCCACCUGAGUGAAGUUCGCUGCUCUGGACAGGAGCUCUCCCUCUGGAAGUGCCCCCACAAGAACAUCACAGCUGAGGAUUGUUCACAUAGCCAGGAUGCCGGGGUCCGGUGCAACCUACCUUACACUGGGGCAGAGACCAGGAUCCGACUCAGUGGGGGCCGCAGCCAACAUGAGGGGCGAGUCGAGGUGCAAAUAGGGGGACCUGGGCCCCUUCGCUGGGGCCUCAUCUGUGGGGAUGACUGGGGGACCCUGGAGGCCAUGGUGGCCUGUAGGCAACUGGGUCUGGGCUACGCCAACCACGGCCUGCAGGAGACCUGGUACUGGGACUCUGGGAAUAUAACAGAGGUGGUGAUGAGUGGAGUGCGCUGCACAGGGACUGAGCUGUCCCUGGAUCAGUGUGCCCAUCAUGGCACCCACAUCACCUGCAAGAGGACAGGGACCCGCUUCACUGCUGGAGUCAUCUGUUCUGAGACUGCAUCAGAUCUGUUGCUGCACUCAGCACUGGUGCAGGAGACCGCCUACAUCGAAGACCGGCCCCUGCAUAUGUUGUACUGUGCUGCGGAAGAGAACUGCCUGGCCAGCUCAGCCCGCUCAGCCAACUGGCCCUAUGGUCACCGGCGUCUGCUCCGAUUCUCCUCCCAGAUCCACAACCUGGGACGAGCUGACUUCAGGCCCAAGGCUGGGCGCCACUCCUGGGUGUGGCACGAGUGCCAUGGGCAUUACCACAGCAUGGACAUCUUCACUCACUAUGAUAUCCUCACCCCAAAUGGCACCAAGGUGGCUGAGGGCCACAAAGCUAGUUUCUGUCUCGAAGACACUGAGUGUCAGGAGGAUGUCUCCAAGCGGUAUGAGUGUGCCAACUUUGGAGAGCAAGGCAUCACUGUGGGUUGCUGGGAUCUCUACCGGCAUGACAUUGACUGUCAGUGGAUUGACAUCACGGAUGUGAAGCCAGGAAACUACAUUCUCCAGGUUGUCAUCAACCCAAACUUUGAAGUAGCAGAGAGUGACUUUACCAACAAUGCAAUGAAAUGUAACUGCAAAUAUGAUGGACAUAGAAUCUGGGUGCACAACUGCCACAUUGGUGAUGCCUUCAGUGAAGAGGCCAACAGGAGGUUUGAACGCUACCCUGGCCAGACCAGCAACCAGAUUAUCUAAGUGCCACUGCCCUCUGCAAACCACCACUGGCCCCUAAUGGCAGGGGUCUGAGGCUGCCAUUACCUCAGGAGCUUACCAAGAAACCCAUGUCAGCAACCGCACUCAUCAGACCAUGCACUAUGGAUGUGGAACUGUCAAGCAGAAGUUUUCACCCUCCUUCAGAGGCCAGCUGUCAGUAUCUGUAGCCAAGCAUGGGAAUCUUUGCUCCCAGGCCCAGCACCGAGCAGAACAGACCAGAGCCCACCACACCACAAAGAGCAGCACCUGACUAACUGCCCACAAAAGAUGGCAGCAGCUCAUUUUCUUUAAUAGGAGGUCAGGAUGGUCAGCUCCAGUAUCUCCCCUAAGUUUAGGGGGAUACAGCUUUACCUCUAGCCUUUUGGUGGGGGAAAAGAUCCAGCCCUCCCACCUCAUUUUUUACUAUAAUAUGUUGCUAGGUAUAAUUUUAUUUUAUAUAAAAAGUGUUUCUGUGAUUCUUCAGAGCCCAGGAGUCAGUGCUGGUGGUUGGAGGGACCUGCCCCCACUGGUUCAUUUAACCCUCUGUCUCGGUGCCCUCAGAACCUCAGCCAGAAAGGCAAGGAGGAAAUCAGAGCAGGAGCCUCAUACUCUUGGUGAUCUAUUCAUUCUGUGACCUCAGGGGUCACAUAUAAGGUCAGUGUUUCUCGUCCCCGCCGGAUCUGCACUGCCAACUGGGAUUGGGUUCGAACAGCUUCAUAAACAUCUUCAGCAUUUUGUACCAUCUGCUCCCCAAUGGCCAAAAUCACAUCACCAGGCCGCAGACCAGCCCUAUAGAGAAAAAUGGACAGAGAGAAAGGAAGGAGUACAAAGCCUAGUUCAAGGACACAUGCACACCUUGCCCAUCCCCAUAUCACACUGCAGCCUCUCCCUCACCGGUGUGCAGGGGAGCCCAGGAUGACUUUAUGGAUGAGUACACCAUGCUGAACAUCGGGAAAGCUUGGUUCUCGAAGCUGUAGUUCAGCAAGGAUGCUGAAAGUACACAGAUCACCCUAUUAGCCAAACCCAGGCAUUCUCCCCAUCCUGAGUUCCACCUCAAGUCUCUCAUCAACACAUUGAUAAAUAUAUGGACAGGACAUGGGCUAGGUACUACAAAAUACAAUGGCAACUCACUUUCUGUCUUCUAGCAAUAAAGUGCAACAUGUACAUAAAAGAUGUACACCACAUGAGGGCACCAAAUGACAAACAGUGUUAAAUCAAUAGCACUAAUGUCAUUCUAGAAUACUAAGAGAAGCUUUAAGGGGAAAGAACUUAAGUUGAGCCUAAAAGGAUGGAUCUGAUAUUAACCAUAUAAAACAAGAACAGCAUAAAUAAAAAACAUGGGAGUAGGAAA